GCAUUUCUCCUCUGUGCUCAUUGCCACAUGCAGCUCAGCCUGGGCUACACAGCCAGGUGUCAGAUGUGUCUCUGCUGAUCUGAGUCUGCCUGUGGCAUGGACCUGCAUCUUCCCUGAAGCAUCUCCAGGGCUGAAAAAUCACUGACCAUGGCACCAUGGUCUCAUCCAUCUGCACAGCUGCAGCCAGUGGGAGGAGACGCCGUGAGCCCUGCCCUCAUGGUUCUGCUCUGCCUCGGGCUGAGUCUGGGCCCCAGGACCCACGUGCAGGCAGGGAACCUCUCCAAAGCCACCCUCUGGGCUGAGCCAGGCUCUGUGAUCAGCCGGGGGAACUCUGUGACCAUCCGGUGUCAGGGGACCCUGGAGGCCCAGGAAUACCGUCUGGUUAAAGAGGGAAGCCCAGAACCCUGGGACACACAGAACCCACUGGAGCCCAAGAACAAGGCCAGAUUCUCCAUCCCAUCCAUGACAGAGCACCAUGCAGGGAGAUACCGCUGUUACUACUACAGCCCUGCAGGCUGGUCAGAGCCCAGCGACCCCCUGGAGCUGGUGGUGACAGGAUUCUACAACAAACCCACCCUCUCAGCCCUGCCCAGUCCUGUGGUGACCUCAGGAGAGAACGUGACCCUCCAGUGUGGCUCACGGCUGAGAUUCGACAGGUUCAUUCUGACUGAGGAAGGAGACCACAAGCUCUCCUGGACCUUGGACUCACAGCUGACCCCCAGUGGGCAGUUCCAGGCCCUGUUCCCUGUGGGCCCUGUGACCCCCAGCCACAGGUGGAUGCUCAGAUGCUAUGGCUCUCGCAGGCAUAUCCUGCAGGUAUGGUCAGAACCCAGUGACCUCCUGGAGAUUCCGGUCUCAGGAGCAGCUGAUAACCUCAGUCCGUCACAAAACAAGUCUGACUCUGGGACUGCCUCACACCUUCAGGAUUACGCAGUAGAGAAUCUCAUCCGCAUGGGCAUGGCCGGCUUGAUCCUGGUGGUCCUUGGGAUUCUGAUAUUUCAGGAUUGGCACAGCCAGAGAAGCCCCCAAGCUGCAGCUGGAAGGUGAACAGAAGAGAGAACAAUGCACCAUUGAAUGCUGGAGCCUUGGAAGCGAAUCUGAUGGUCCUAGGAGGUUCGGGAAGACCAUCUGAGGCCUAUGCCAUCUGGACUGUCUGCUGGCAAUUUCUUUUUUUCUUUCUUUUCUUUUCUUUCUUUUUUUUUUUUUUUUUUUUUUUUUUGAGAUGGAGUCUUGCUCUGUCACCAGGCUGGAAUGCAGUGGCGCAAUCUGGGCUCACUGCAACCUCCGCCUCUCGGGUUCAAGUGAUUCUCCUGCCUCAGCCUCUGGCAAUUUCUAGAGGGAGGAAUGGGUGUUUGAGUGCAGAGACACUGGUCUGGGGUGAUCCAUGGAGGA